AACAAAGAAGCGAACGCGGGAGCAGGGUGCGCGAGAGCGCGCCCUCCGCAGACAGGUUGAGCGAGCGGGAGAGGCCCGGGGCACGUGCAGAAAGGAGCCCCGCGAGUGGCGCGCCGGGGAUGUGAGUGCCCCUUGCCCUCUACUGAAUCCAGCCCCCUCCCCGCCCACCGCCUCCGCCUUUGCAUAGAUACAGUCAUCUGGCCAGCCCCCGCCCCUCCUCCCGGCGUCAGCCCGCCAGAGGCCGCGCGGGGCCCGGGCUUCGGCCGAUCAGCCCGGGAGGCCCCGCCGCGCCCCCUUGGCCCGCGCGCCCGUGGUCACAGUGGAAGAGGCGCCCGCGCUGCGCUGCCCGGAGGAGCCGUCGCGCGCCCGCUUCCUGUUCGGCUGGUUCCUGCCAGCUCGAGGACAAAACACGCGUGCGCGCGGCGGGCGAGCGCGCUCGCCGCCUCAGUCGCCAGCGCCGGGCGCAGUCCGCCUUUUUCCGGAGCAGACUGGCCGCGGUGCUAGUCGGUAGCAGCGGCCGCCGCAGCGGCUCCGCACUGGCGAACCGAGGGCAGAAAAAGGCGGGGUUGACGGCUUUUUGGUAGGAGUGGGCUGGACCGGACGCCAGAGACAAAGGCUCCCAAGGCAAGAGGGACUGUGGCCCUGCGUCGGCUCUGCUCGGGACUGCUGACCCCAGGAAUUUACGCCCCUUCGUUUUUCUCUUCUGAUUCUUCUCUUCUCCCAAGCCCGCGUCCCCUCACGCGUGGCCUCUCUCCUUGCCGGGAGGGCCGCGAUGGAGGUCCCGCCCAGGCUUUCCCAUGUGCCGCCGCCAUUGUUCCCCUCCGCUCCCGCUACUUUAGCCUCCCGCAGCCUCUCCCAUUGGCGGCCGCGGCCGCCGCGGCAGCUAGCCCCGCUCCUCCCUUCGCUCGCUCCCAGCUCCGCCCGGCAGGGGGCGCGCCGGGCCCAGCGCCACGUCACCGCCCAGCAGCCCUCCCGAUUGGCGGGCGGGGCGGCUAUAAAGGGAGGGCGCAGGCGGCGCCCGGAUCUCUUCCGCCGCCAUUUUAAAUCCAGCUCCAUACAACGCUCCGCCGCCGCUGCUGCCGCGACCCGGACUGCGCGCCAGCACCCCCCUGCCGACAGCUCCGUCACUAUGGAGGAUAUGAACGAGUACAGCAAUAUAGAGGAAUUCGCAGAGGGAUCCAAGAUCAACGCGAGCAAGAAUCAGCAGGAUGACGGUAAAAUGUUUAUUGGAGGCUUGAGCUGGGAUACAAGCAAAAAAGAUCUGACAGAGUACUUGUCUCGAUUUGGGGAAGUUGUAGACUGCACAAUUAAAACAGAUCCAGUCACUGGGAGAUCAAGAGGAUUUGGAUUUGUGCUUUUCAAAGAUGCUGCUAGUGUUGAUAAGGUUUUGGAACUGAAAGAACACAAACUGGAUGGCAAAUUGAUAGAUCCCAAAAGGGCCAAAGCUUUAAAAGGGAAAGAACCUCCCAAAAAGGUUUUUGUGGGUGGAUUGAGCCCGGAUACUUCUGAAGAACAAAUUAAAGAAUAUUUUGGAGCCUUUGGAGAGAUUGAAAAUAUUGAACUUCCCAUGGAUACAAAAACAAAUGAAAGAAGAGGAUUUUGUUUUAUCACAUAUACUGAUGAAGAGCCAGUAAAAAAAUUGUUAGAAAGCAGAUACCAUCAAAUUGGUUCUGGGAAGUGUGAAAUCAAAGUUGCACAACCCAAAGAGGUAUAUAGGCAGCAACAGCAACAACAAAAAGGUGGAAGAGGUGCUGCAGCUGGUGGACGAGGUGGUACGAGGGGUCGUGGCCGAGGUCAGGGCCAAAACUGGAACCAAGGAUUUAAUAACUAUUAUGAUCAAGGAUAUGGAAAUUACAAUAGUGCCUAUGGUGGUGAUCAAAACUAUAGUGGCUAUGGCGGAUAUGAUUAUACUGGGUAUAACUAUGGGAACUAUGGAUAUGGACAGGGAUAUGCAGACUACAGUGGCCAACAGAGCACUUAUGGCAAGGCAUCUCGAGGGGGUGGCAAUCACCAAAACAAUUACCAGCCAUACUAAAGGAGAACAUUGGAGAAAACAGGAGGAGAUGUUAAAGUAACCCAUCUUGCAGGACGACAUUGAAGAUUGGUCUUCUGUUGAUCUAAGAUGAUUAUUUUGUAAAAGACUUUCUAGUGUACAAGACACCAUUGUGUCCAACUGUAUAUAGCUGCCAAUUAGUUUUCUUUGUUUUUACUUUGUCCUUUGCUAUCUGUGUUAUGACUCAAUGUGGAUUUGUUUAUACACAUUUUAUUUGUAUCAUUUCAUGUUAAACCUCAAAUAAAUGCUUCCUUAUGUGAUUGCUUUUCUGCGUCAGGUACUACAUAGCUCUGUAAAAAAUGUAAUUUAAAAUAAGCAAUAAUUAAGGCACAGUUGAUUUUGUAGAGUAUUGGUCCAUACAGAGAAACUGUGGUCCUUUAUAAAUAGCCAGCCAGCGUCACCCUCUUCUCCAAUUUGUAGGUGUAUUUUAUGCUCUUAAGGCUUCAUCUUCUCCCUGUAACUGAGAUUUCUACCACACCUUUGAACAAUGUUCUUUCCCUUCUGGUUAUCUGAAGACUGUCCUGAAAGGAAGACAUAAGUGUUGUGAUUAGUAGAAGCUUUCUAGUAGACCAUAUUUCUUCUGGAUUGUAAUAAAAUUGUUAGUAGCUCCUUUUACUUUGUUCCUGUCUCUGGAAAGCCAUUUUUGAAUUGCUGAUUACUUUGGCUUUAAUCAGUGGUCACCUAGAAAAAGCUUUGUAAUCAUAACACAAUGAGUAAUUCUUGAUAAAAGUUCAGAUACAAAAGGAGCACUGUAAAACUGGUAGGAGCUAUGGUUUAAGAGCAUUGGAAGUAGUUACAACUCAAGGAUUUUGGUAGAAAGGUAUGAGUUUGGUCGAAAAAUUAAAAUAGUGGCAAAAUAAGAUUUAGUUGUGUUUUCUCAGAGCCGCCACAAGAUUGAACAAAAUGUUUUCUGUUUGGGCAUCCUGAGGAAGUUGUAUUAGCUGUUAAUGCUCUGUGAGUUUAGAAAAAGUCUUGAUAGUAAAUCUAGUUUUUGACACAGUGCAUGAACUAAGUAGUUAAAUAUUUACAUAUUCAGAAAGGAAUAGUGGAAAAGGUAUCUUGGUUAUGACAAAGUCAUUACAAAUGUGACUAAGUCAUUACAAAUGUGACUGAGUCAUUACAGUGGACCCUCUGGGUGCAUUGAAAAGAAUCCGUUUUAUAUCCAGGUUUCAGAGGACCUGGAAUAAUAAAAAGCUUUGGAUUUUGCAUUCAGUGUAGUUGGAUUUUGGGACCUUGGCCUCAGUGUUAUUUACUGGGAUUGGCAUACGUGUUCACAGGCAGAGUAGUUGAUCUCACACAACGGGUGAUCUCACAAAACUGGUAAGUUUCUUAUGCUCAUGAGCCCUCCCUUUUUUUUUUUAAUUUGGUGCCUGCAACUUUCUUAACAAUGAUUCUACUUCCUGGGCUAUCACAUUAUAAUGCUCUUGGCCUCUUUUUUGCUGCUGUUUUGCUAUUCUUAAACUUAGGCCAAGUACCAAUGUUGGCUGUUAGAAGGGAUUCUGUUCAUUCAACAUGCAACUUUAGGGAAUGGAAGUAAGUUCAUUUUUAAGUUGUGUUGUCAGUAGGUGCGGUGUCUAGGGUAGUGAAUCCUGUAAGUUCAAAUUUAUGAUUAGGUGACGAGUUGACAUUGAGAUUGUCCUUUUCCCUGAUCAAAAAAUGAAUAAAGCCUUUUUAAACAAAAUCCAAACUUUUAAUCAAGUCUUGAUAUGUAUGACUGAGAAAAAAUACACUACAUCUAGAGAUGAUUGAGAUGUUUUGCAAAGAAUUGAAGGGGGAGUGAGAAUUGGUUUUUCUUGCAGGGGCUUUGAACUCUAGAUUUGGGCUUUGAACUCUAGAUUUAAUUCAGAUUUCAGGGUCUAUCAGUUCACCAACUGAUGCAAAUUUGAACAGAUACUCUAAGGCUAAGUGUCCUAGGUUGGAUGAACUGAAGCUACUAUCAAGAUCUCGUUCCCAAGGAUUAAUUUAGAACAAAGUAAUUGGACAAGUUUAUUGGGGAGGGGAUAGAAAUGAAUUCUAAAGUACCUAUAACAAAUACUCUGUGUAUGUUUUUUACAUCGUAUUUGCCUUUUACAUUGUUUAGACCAAAUUCUGUGUGAUGUUAUCCUCGGGAAGAGGAUAGAAAUUAAUUCUAAAGUACCUAUAACAAAUGCUCGGUUUGUAUAUGUUUUUAUACAUCGUAUUUGCCUUUUGCAUUGUUCAGACCAAAUUCUGUGUGAUGUUAUCCUAACAAAACACCUUAGUAAUUUCUUUGGUUAACAUGUUAAUCUGUAAUCUCACUUUUAUAAGAUGAGGACUAUUAAAAUGAGAUGUCUGUUGGGA